AUAGUAACCGCACCCAUAACAGCCGUGGUGGUUAUGGCUGGCCUGAGCGGCGCGCAGAUCCCCGACGGGGAGUUCACCGCGGUCGUGUACCGCCUCAUCCGCAAUGCACGCUACGCCGAGGCGGUGCAGCUGCUGGGCGGAGAACUGCAGCGGAGCCCUAGGAGCCGCGCCGGCCUGUCGCUGCUAGGCUACUGCUACUACCGCCUGCAGGAGUUCGCGCUGGCGGCCGAGUGCUAUGAGCAGCUGGGCCAGCUGCACCCGGAACUGGAGCAGUACCGCCUGUACCAGGCCCAGGCCCUGUACAAGGCCUGCCUUUAUGCGGAGGCCACCCGGGUCGCCUUCCUUCUCCUGGAUAACCCCGCCUACCACAGCCGGGUCCUCCGCCUGCAAGCUGCUAUCAAGUACAGCGAGGGCGAUCUGCCAGGGUCCAGGAGCCUGGUAGAGCAGCUGCCGAGUAGGGAAGGGGGAGAGGAAAGUGGGGGCGAGAAUGAGACCGAUGGCCAGAUCAACCUGGGUUGUUUGCUCUACAAGGAGGGACAGUAUGAAGCUGCAUGCUCCAAGUUUUUUGCCGCCCUGCAGGCCUCGGGCUACCAGCCUGACCUUUCCUACAACCUGGCUUUGGCCUAUUACAGCAGCCGACAGUAUGCUUCAGCACUGAAGCAUAUCGCUGAGAUUAUUGAGCGUGGCAUCCGCCAGCACCCUGAGCUAGGUGUGGGCAUGACCACUGAGGGCAUUGAUGUUCGCAGUGUUGGCAACACCUUAGUCCUCCAUCAGACUGCUCUGGUGGAAGCCUUCAACCUUAAGGCAGCUAUAGAAUACCAACUGAGAAACUAUGAGGCAGCUCAAGAAGCCCUCACUGACAUGCCACCCAGGGCAGAGGAAGAGUUGGACCCUGUGACCCUACACAACCAGGCACUAAUGAACAUGGAUGCCAGGCCUACAGAAGGGUUUGAAAAGCUACAGUUUUUGCUCCAACAGAAUCCCUUUCCUCCAGAGACUUUUGGCAACCUGUUGCUGCUCUACUGUAAAUAUGAGUAUUUUGACCUGGCAGCAGAUGUCCUGGCAGAAAAUGCCCAUUUGAUUUAUAAGUUCCUCACACCCUAUCUCUAUGACUUCUUGGACGCUGUGAUCACUUGCCAGACAGCUCCUGAAGAGGCUUUCAUUAAGCUUGAUGGGCUAGCAGGGAUGCUGACUGAGGUCCUCCGGAAACUUACCAUACAAGUACAGGAAGCAAGACACAAUAGAGAUGAUGAAGCUAUCAAAAAGGCAGUGAAUGAAUAUGAUGAAACCAUGGAGAAAUACAUUCCUGUGUUGAUGGCUCAGGCAAAAAUCUACUGGAAUCUUGAAAAUUAUCCAAUGGUGGAAAAGAUCUUCCGCAAAUCUGUGGAAUUCUGUAACGACCAUGAUGUGUGGAAGUUGAAUGUGGCUCAUGUUCUGUUCAUGCAGGAAAACAAAUACAAAGAAGCCAUUGGUUUCUAUGAACCCAUAGUCAAGAAGCAUUAUGAUAACAUCCUGAAUGUCAGUGCUAUUGUACUGGCUAAUCUCUGUGUUUCCUAUAUUAUGACAAGUCAAAAUGAAGAAGCAGAGGAGUUGAUGAGGAAGAUUGAAAAGGAGGAAGAGCAGCUCUCUUAUGAUGACCCAGAUAAGAAAAUGUACCAUCUCUGCAUUGUGAAUUUGGUGAUAGGAACUCUUUAUUGUGCCAAAGGAAAUUAUGACUUUGGUAUUUCUCGAGUUAUCAAAAGCUUGGAACCUUACAACAAAAAGCUGGGAACAGACACCUGGUAUUAUGCCAAAAGAUGCUUCCUGUCCUUGUUAGAAAACAUGUCAAAACACACAAUCAUGCUUCGUGAUAGUGUUAUUCAAGAAUGUGUCCAGUUUCUAGAACACUGUGAACUUCAUGGCAGAAACAUACCUGCUGUUAUUGAACAACCCCUGGAAGAAGAAAGAAUGCAUGUUGGAAAGAAUACAGUCACAUAUGAGUCUAGGCAGUUAAAAGCUUUGAUUUAUGAGAUUAUAGGAUGGAAUAUAUAGUAAUAGCUGAUAGUGGCAUUUAUCAAAUGGCUUUGUUAUGUAAAUUUGCAUCGCUUUAUUUACCCUUUGGCAUCUUUAUAUUUGUUACAUGUUGAACUUUGUACACUUAUGCAUUAUAAAAAAAAAAGUAGCUAAAACUUUUGCUGUUAAAUUUCCCAGAAAGUGACAUAUUCUAAGAACUUUUACCCCAGGAGUUAUGAAAAAUUCCAAACUUAUGAGGAAUGUUUAUAUCAGAAGUUGUAAUACGUUUGUUUCCUUUCCUCUGUUAUCUUUUGUGCUUUGACGUAUCUUGAGGGGUCUUUGCACAAGGAUUACAUCAUUCAGGGACCAAGCACUAUCUCAGUAAUAGUUAAGAGUAGUCUUUAAAUAAUCAUUUCAGGGAUUGUGUGAGAGUAGUCUCACAAUUUACACUCAUUAAUUUGUAAUGCAUACUUUUUAUAUAGACUUUAGGAUAUUUUGGCAGUGUUUAUUCAUAUGGAUAUAAUUCUUUACCUAACCAAAAUUCCUUAGGUUAUAAGUGGUUUUAACGUGCAAAAGUCAGUAAAAAAUUUUGUUGCCUUAACAAAAUUAUGGUGCUAUAAUGUAGAGACAAUGAACGAUUAUCAAAGAACAAAUUUCCCUGGUUUUCUUUUGUUCCCUUUAAUAAUUUAAAUAUAUGAACAAGAUACACUGUUACUAUUUUCCAUGAUAACUUUUUAAAUAUCUCUGUGAGAAAUAACAGAGCUAUCCUGAGAACUCAGGGGUUUGUUUAAGAGACACAGGUUUUGUUAUGUUUGUUGCCCAGGCUAGUAUCCAGCUCCUAGGCUUAAGCAUACUCCCACUUCAGCUUCCCAAGUAGCUGGGACUACUGGCACAAAUCACUGGGUCCAGUUCUCAGUUCUUAAUUCCUACCUUUGUGUUUGCAAUUUAGGAUAUGCUGGCUGUACAGUGUUUCCAUGUUGUAGCCUCUUGAAUAAGGAAAAAUCUCAGCCACCAGGUCUGACCAAAAAGGUCAAUUCUAAGUUGUAAUGUUCAUUUCAUGUCCGCAACUCCCAAGAGUUAUUUGGAGUUCCCACUGGGAACCACAUGCAUUCUGAUCAGGCAUUUUAUUUUCUGAACCUUACAAGAGCCUUACUAUUUGAUUUCCCACUCCUCACUCCUCUCUUCCCACAAAAAGUAACUGUCAAUCCUAACUUGACCUGGCUUAGAAAAAUCAAGUGUAUUAGACUGAAUCAUAUGCAGUUGUUGAUUUUGACAGUUUUUGAUGUACAAAACUAGCAGUUUCUCAUAGCUCAACCUAGUAGCUUUCUUCUGAAUGAUAGGGAACCUCUGCCAUAAUGAGAUGAUUUUUUCCUUCAAGGAAAAGGAACCACUUAGCCACAUAAGUACUGAUAAGAAACAUGCUCAGCAUAAUUCCUCUGUAGCAUGACCUCCUGAGUGCUCAAAUUGUAUUAUACCAGGAAAUUUGGCUUAUUGUGAAGUUCAAUGGUUUUGAAUUUAUGGCAUUUUAAAUCUUAAUUAUCUGAGCUGCUAUCAUUUACCACUGAUGCUUUAGUCUCACAUGUGGAGGACAAGCAAUGUUUAGUGACCUCUUCACUGCAUCCCAUAGCACAUUCAAUGUCUGGGAAAUGUUCUUUGUUUGACAACUUCUGUACUAAAAGUGUUGCUGCAGUAGCUUUGUGCCCCUGUCAGUCUUGGUAGCCCCUUAAGAUUUGGAAAGUAAAUGAACUGAAAUCUUGUUUUCAAUGGCCAUAUUAAAAUUCUUUUUUUUUUUCCUGUUUCUUCUAAA